GCGGGCCGGUGGCUAUGGAGGCGGCGGCGGUUGAUGGUUGACCGUUGGCUCCGGGGUGGGGGUCGCCGUUCGAGUGAUCUGCUCAGACCCGACCAGAGGGCGCGGGCUGCUGAUGCUUGGCUUGGAGCCCGUGGGGGAGACCUAGUUCGGCUCCGCCAUGCCGGCCGCCGGGAGUAACGAGCCGGACGGCGUCCUCAGCUAUCAGAGACCAGAUGAAGAAGCUGUGGUGGAUCAGGGUGGGACCAGUACAAUUCUCAACAUUCACUAUGAAAAAGAAGAGCUGGAAGGUCACAGAACUCUGUAUGUGGGAGUUCGGAUGCCGCUUGGCCGGCAGAGCCAUCGGCAUCACCGCACUCAUGGCCAGAAGCACCGGAGACGAGGGCGGGGCAAAGGAGCCAGCCAGGGGGAGGAAGGCCUGGAAGCCCUGGCCCACGACACACCAUCUCAGCGUGUUCAGUUCAUUCUUGGCACCGAGGAAGAUGAAGAGCAUGUGCCUCAUGAGCUGUUUACAGAGCUGGAUGAGAUCUGUAUGAAAGAGGGAGAAGAUGCUGAGUGGAAGGAAACAGCCAGGUGGCUGAAGUUUGAAGAAGAUGUUGAAGAUGGGGGAGAACGCUGGAGCAAGCCUUAUGUGGCAACCCUUUCAUUGCACAGCCUGUUUGAGCUAAGGAGCUGCCUUAUUAAUGGAACAGUCCUCCUGGAUAUGCAUGCAAAUAGCAUAGAAGAAAUUUCAGACCUGAUCCUGGAUCAGCAAGAACUGUCCAGUGACCUGAAUGACAGCAUGAGGGUUAAAGUGCGGGAAGCCCUUCUCAAAAAGCAUCAUCAUCAGAAUGAAAAGAAGAGAAACAACCUCAUUCCCAUUGUUCGCUCCUUUGCUGAGGUUGGCAAGAAGCAGUCUGAUCCUCAUUUGAUGGAUAAACAUGGUCAAACCGUGUCUCCUCAGUCUGUUCCAACUACAAAUCUUGAAGUAAAAAAUGGAGUGAAUUGUGAACAUAGUCCUGUGGAUUUAAGCAAGGUAGACCUUCAUUUCAUGAAAAAAAUUCCUACUGGGGCCGAGGCCUCCAAUGUCCUGGUUGGAGAGGUGGAUAUUUUGGACCGUCCCAUUGUUGCCUUUGUGAGGCUGUCUCCAGCUGUUCUUCUCUCAGGCCUAACAGAAGUGCCAAUCCCAACAAGAUUUUUGUUUAUCUUAUUGGGUCCAGUAGGGAAAGGUCAGCAGUACCAUGAGAUUGGCAGAUCCAUGGCCACCAUCAUGACAGAUGAGAUUUUUCAUGACGUAGCAUAUAAGGCAAAAGAGCGAGAUGAUCUCCUGGCGGGGAUUGAUGAGUUCCUAGACCAGGUGACGGUGCUCCCUCCAGGAGAGUGGGAUCCCUCCAUUAGAAUUGAGCCACCCAAAAAUGUCCCUUCCCAGGAGAAAAGGAAAAUGCCUGGAGUUCCAAAUGGAAAUGUUUGCCACAUAGAACAGGAACCACAUGGGGGUCACAGUGGGCCAGAACUUCAGCGCACUGGGCGGCUAUUUGGGGGCUUGGUGCUGGACAUCAAGCGGAAGGCCCCCUGGUACUGGAGCGACUACCGAGAUGCACUCAGCUUACAGUGUUUGGCUUCCUUUCUGUUCCUGUACUGUGCCUGCAUGUCACCUGUCAUCACCUUUGGGGGACUGCUUGGAGAAGCCACUGAGGGACGCAUAAGUGCAAUUGAAUCCUUGUUUGGAGCUUCCAUGACUGGGAUUGCUUAUUCCUUGUUUGCGGGACAGGCUCUCACCAUCCUGGGAAGUACUGGACCAGUGCUUGUGUUUGAAAAGAUUUUGUUCAAAUUCUGCAAAGACUAUGCUCUUUCAUACCUCUCCCUGCGAGCUUGUAUUGGACUGUGGACCGCUUUCCUGUGUAUUGUCCUUGUGGCAACUGAUGCCAGUUCCCUUGUCUGCUACAUUACCCGUUUCACUGAAGAAGCAUUUGCCUCCCUAAUUUGCAUUAUUUUCAUCUAUGAAGCAAUAGAAAAACUGAUUCACCUGGCAGAGACCUACCCCAUCCACAUGCACAGCCAGCUGGACCACCUUAGCCUCUAUUACUGCAGGUGUACUCUGCCAGAGAAUCCAAACAAUCACACCCUCCAGUACUGGAAGGACCACAACAUCGUGACAGCAGAAGUCCACUGGGCUAACCUGACUGUCAGUGAAUGCCAGGAGAUGCAUGGAGAGUUCAUGGGAUCUGCGUGCGGCCAUCAUGGACCCUACACUCCUGAUGUCCUCUUUUGGUCCUGUAUUCUCUUUUUCACCACCUUCAUCCUCUCAAGCACCUUAAAGACGUUUAAGACGAGCCGUUAUUUCCCAACCAGAGUACGCUCCAUGGUGAGUGACUUUGCUGUUUUCCUCACUAUCUUCACAAUGGUGAUUAUUGAUUUUUUGAUUGGAGUCCCAUCACCAAAGCUUCAAGUUCCCAGUGUGUUCAAGCCAACAAGGGAUGAUCGCGGAUGGAUUAUUAAUCCCAUUGGCCCCAAUCCCUGGUGGACUGUGAUAGCUGCAAUUAUCCCAGCUCUUCUCUGUACUAUCUUGAUAUUCAUGGAUCAGCAGAUCACAGCCGUCAUUAUUAACAGGAAGGAACAUAAGCUCAAGAAAGGCUGUGGCUACCACCUGGACCUACUGAUGGUGGCCAUCAUGCUGGGUGUCUGCUCCAUCAUGGGCCUGCCCUGGUUUGUAGCUGCAACUGUCUUGUCCAUCACACAUGUGAACAGCCUCAAGCUAGAAUCUGAAUGCUCUGCUCCUGGAGAACAGCCCAAGUUCCUGGGCAUCCGAGAACAGAGAGUGACAGGCCUUAUGAUCUUUGUGCUGAUGGGCUGCUCAGUCUUCAUGACGGCUAUCUUAAAGUUUAUUCCAAUGCCAGUACUCUACGGAGUUUUCCUUUACAUGGGAGUUUCUUCACUACAGGGAAUUCAGUCUCAGUUUCCAUUUCUGUCCAGAGGAAAUGGUGUUACCUACCUUUCAGAGCAGUUCUUUGAUCGUCUAAAGCUCUUUGGGAUGCCCGCAAAGCACCAGCCAGAUUUCAUCUACCUGCGGCAUGUGCCGCUGCGCAAAGUGCACCUCUUCACCCUCAUCCAGUUGACCUGUCUCGUCCUGCUCUGGGUCAUCAAGGCAUCUCCAGCUGCCAUUGUUUUCCCAAUGAUGGUUUUGGCCUUGGUCUUUGUCAGGAAAGUCAUGGAUCUCUGUUUCUCUAAGCGAGAGCUGAGCUGGCUAGAUGAUCUCAUGCCUGAAAGCAAAAAGAAGAAGUUGGAUGAUGCCAAAAAGAAGGCCAAGGAGGAAGAGGAGGCUGAGAAAAUGUUAGAAAUUGGGGGAGACAAGUUUCCCUUAGAGAGCAGGAAGUUACUAAGUAGUCCUGGAAAGAACAUCAGUUGCAGAUGUGACCCCUCUGAGAUUAAUAUAUCUGAUGAAAUGCCUAAAACUACAGUUUGGAAAGCUCUCAGUAUGAAUUCUGGAAAUGCAAAGGAAAAGAGUCUCUUCAACUAAGAGUCUUUGCUGGGAUGGAAGAUUUGGGCCGUGUGGUGCCUCAGGGAAGUUCUGGUUACAGAGAAAAUGGCGAGUCUCUCAGAGAAGAAGCAAGACCAAGUCUGGCCCUGUCCUUGGUCAUCUCAAAGCCAUGCCGAAGCAUUCAGUUAUUCUUGGUGUGCAUUGGAAGGCAUCCAGCUAUCCCCAUACCAGCAGCCAGUCACCAGAUGUGAAUGUGGAAGCAGAAGACCACCUCCUGUUGGUUCUUCUCCUCUUCCUUCUUUUUCUCUUUAGAACGGCCACCAUUGAAGACCUAGCUUCCCAUUUUCCAGACGUUUUCUCUGAAAUUCUCUGCUGGCCUGCCAAGCCAUAUGGAUUCAUUCUGCCACUGAGGAGUCCUUCAGUGAGGUCCCUCUUCCUAAAGGACAGAGUGGGGAGUAGGAGGGGAACAGAGAGGACAUCCUCUCUGGCUCUCCAGUGCUCUUAGUGUCUACAGGCUCCUAGGCAGCCCUGGGCCUUGGUUUGAUUACCUCCCCUGGGGGAUGCUGGUCAGACCCAGAGGUUGUCAGGAGGUCAGCUACCAGGAAGAUCCAUGAUCUGGGCAUUGGCAGUGCCUGCCACCACAGCCAGGAAGAUGCCUCUGACCUGGGUGCAUCUCCAUCACUCCUUAGCAGCAGCCUGCAUAACUGGCAAGAAUCUUGGAUGAUACAAGAGCCAAGAAGGGACAUUUGAGUUGUGUCGCUUAGAUAGGAAAGGGAUCCAGGGAAAAUCAACAGUAAGUGAGGAUGAGCAGUGUCUCUUGGUUUUCAUUGAGGAUAGAGUAAGAGAUUGAGUUUAGAUUGCAACAGAAGGAAUUAGUUUAGAUACCAGGAAGAACUUCCUAGCCUGAAGAUUUGUCAUAGUGUCUGCUUUCUAGAUAUCUGGGAAAGAUUUGAUAAUAGUUGUUUGUGAAUAGAAAGGAGGAUAUGAUGUUUUUAUUGGCCAUUUUGCGGGACUCUUCGACUUCUUGCUGCUGUCUCUUGAGGAUACAUUCCAAUUCCAUCCUGGCGAGAUCCAAGUGCUUACGUACUGUCUCCUUAGCUGCCUUAGAGUAAACGAUCAUCAGUUCAAUGGACCAAAAUCACCUUCAGCCAUGUGGUUUCUUCAUCAUCAUGGAUUUCUUUUGGUUGACAAACAUUCUGGCUCUCAGAUGCAAAAAGUCACACUGGGAAAUGAACUGUAAGUGGUGAAAUUAGUUUUGGUAUUUAAUUUAAAACUACAUUUAUAGUUUUUCUCUUCUCUUCUAUGUUGCAAUGAAUGUAAAGUAUUUGGGAUCCAGUGCUUAUAAACCUUUCCUUCCUUUGUGCACAGAAUGUAACUAGCAAGCCCAUUAGCACCCAGAUAAUUCUAUCAUGUUAGUUUCCCAUCCUGGAAAAUCUUUGUACAGUGGGAAGUUCCCCGAUGUGUUUUUCUUUCUUAGGUGAAGGGUUGGCUAUAUCACUUUAUUGAAUUUUGCAUUCCUUAGACUUUUAAAAUAUACUAAUGUAUUCUAGUCUUACUCUAAAGACCUUUGAUGUUAAAGGAAUCCUUCAUUUAUUUCAUAUUCCCUAUCUCAUAGGGCCACAAUUAUUUUAAUACAGAGAUGAUUUUCAAAAUAUUUUAACAACUGGUACAGGACAGAUGCCAGCCACUCAGAAGGGAUGCCUGCUGUAAACAAGCAGUAUGUAUGGUUGUACCAAUGCCUAUUGGCUGAACAUUAUGCUACUUUCAGAUAUUAAAAUGGUGUUCCUUUGAAUCGUGGGUAUUGUUCCUGGUUUGUCUCAUUUCUAUCACAAGGCUGUUUUGGGCACAGCCUUAGCUUCCUUUCAUAUAUAUAUGGUGCAGACAGGAUAGGUCAUGCUUCUUGGAACCUAUAUGGGCAUUAAAAUCUUCAUGAGCCAAAGCUUCACAUUUUAGCACUUUAGGAUAACUGUAGUAAUUGUACUCAUUUACCUACCUAAUUGGGAAGAAUUAAAAGGCAGCCCAUCUGGAGGAUAAGCUUUCUUGCAGACUUUUCCCUUGUCCCUCUCUGGCUGCCUCCUUGAGCUUGCCACUUUUUCAUCUUCAUUGUUCCCUGAGAACAUCUCCCCUUUCUUGCUCUAUCUUGCCCCUCCCAUCUUUUCCUGCCACCUCUGUGUGGGGAGGUUGAUGACCAUUUCACCUCUUUCCCUAGCCUCAGCACAGCUGUAAGGAGUGUAUCAAAACUGGGUGAGAGUAUCACUCAGAAAAAUGCCUCCCCUAACACACGGAUGUCUUGUGCUGCCUUGACCGCUUGAGGGGAGGAGCCUUCAUUAACUCUGUGUAGUGCAGGUACAGGACCACCUGUGCACUUUAGGGUACUUCUCGAGCUAGACCCUCCUGGAUCACUGCGCCUUAGGAAUGUUAGCUACUUUUUAAAAAAAAUAUGAUUUGGUGCGUUGUUGGGGUGAACUCCAUGGGGAAGAUUGUGAGUGAAGAUGGGAAGGAAUUUGGGUGGUUUUGCCACGAGGUGAUGGUUGGGGUUGGGCGAAUGGGUUGGAUGAUCCUGGCUCUGUGGGUGUGGUGCUCGGUUGCCUCCGUACAGUUGCAGUUCACCUUUGUGCAUGGUGAUUACCAGUCACUCUAGGGAUUGUAGGUCCCAACAGCGGUUCCAGCAGCCUGCACAGCUGGUACGAGGACAGCUGGAGGAGGGUCUGAUAUCCCUGCAAGUGAUGCAGGAUAAAACUUCCCGGCCGGGCGCAAUGGCUCGCGCCUGUAAUCCCAGCACUUUGGGAGGCCAAGAUGGGCGGAUCACGAGGUCAGGAGAUCGAGACCAUCCUGGCUAACGUGGUGAAACCCCGUCUCUACUAAAAAUACAAAAAAAUUAGCUGGGCAUGGUGGCGGGCGCCUGUAGUCCCAGCUAUUCAGGAGGCUGAGGCAGAAUGGCGUGAACGCGGGAGGCAGAGCUUGCAGUGAGCCGAGAUCAUGCCACUGCACUCCAGCCUGGGUGACAGAGCAAGACUCCAUUUCAAAAAAAAAAAAAAAAAAAAACUUCCCAAUAGGAGGUAUUCCUUGAUGGCUCUCGAAUGCAUGAAUGAUAUAUCAAUUUGAAGUUUCUCGACCUUUCCAUCAAGGAUCUUGAAUUUUUUCUCAAUUAUGCUUGCUAAUGUGUCAAAGGCCAAGUACACUGUAUCAAACUUGCCGUCUGUAAGAUGCAAGAUCAAUCUAGUGUUUCAGCCAGUUCACUACUGACAUCAGACUCAACUUUGUCCCCUCUCUUUCUUUUCAUGCAAGAGACUUUAAGGGUAACCUCUUCAGUUGAAACUGUCUUGGAAGUGCAGCCCUCCUCCUGUGUGGCUAGAGAAAGAGAUGGCACCAGGAUCUCUUAACGGCAAGUGCUCACGGGGCAUGGGUGAUUUUGUCUAGUCUGGUCCUUUUGGACGUGGUGAUUUCCUGUCAUCCUCGUGGUCUGACAUUGCUUCUCACUGGAUACUGGUUGUGGCCUUUGACUCAUUAGCUGAUUGUUGGAUCUCUUUGUGAGGUUCGAUUUUUUAAAAAUCCAUGGGUCCCUAUGGACUGUCACCUGUUGCAGAUGAUGGUGAUUCUCUUCUUUUUUUUGUCUCCAAUAGUUGCCUGGACGACUUCAUGGGUCAGUCCACAUGAUUGCAGGAUUUCCCAUUGUUCAUCUGUGAAUGUUGAUUGGCCAACCUGUCUGAGCUUUCAGCAGAUGCAUCCUUGAGCUUACUUUCAGGAAUUCCUCCUGGAAUUGGUUUUCCUUGGUGGUAAUUUCUCAUGGUGGAGCUUGUUUCUGAGGCAUGGUACAGUGCUGCGGAGGCAAGGCAAGGCUGUCAUGGUGAUUUUCACAGCAUCUGGAUGGCAAAUUGCCUUCACGUAGGGAAACCACAUGGGACUGAUAGCUUUCUCAAGGGAUCUCCAAGCAUCUCUGAAUUUGGGGAUUUCAUCAGUUACUCCUGGAAUCAAAAUGAGUGUGGAGUCAUAAUAUAUAUUUUUUUUGAGACAAAGUCUCACUCUGUCGCCCAGGCUGGAGUGCAGUGGUGCGAUCUCAUCUCACUGCAACCUCUGCCUCCUGGGUUCAAGUGAUUCUCCUGCCUCAGCCUCCCAAGUAGCUAGGAUUACAGGUGCGCACCACCAUGCCCAGCUAAUUUUUGUAUUUUAGUAGAGACGAAGUUUCACUAUGUUGGCCAGGCUGGUCUGAAACUCCUGGCCUCAGGUGAUCCACCCACCUCAGCCUCCCAAAGUGCUGGGAUUACAGGUAUGAGCCACUGCCCCUGGCCUCAAAAUCUUUAAGGAAGUUAUUUAUCGUCACAAGUGUUGUCAUCUGUGACUCAUGGGCCACUUGAUGAACCUGAACCAUUAGUGGUUGUCCAGAUCCUCCAACUUUUUCAGGCAGUAUUCCAAUCAGGGUUUUACGACACCAGGGUAUCCCACCUUUUUUGCAACAUAGGCAGAAACACCAAGCUGUGGGUAAUUGAUGUGCGUGUCACUGAUUCCUGCAACAGCUUUGAAUGUAUUAAAUCUGUUUUCAACAGCCCUUGCAUAGGUGUUAUCUCUCAAAUCUCUGUAAAGAGCACUAAGAGUAUGUAGUGUUGCAUGAUAUAAUCCAAGCCUGUGGGCUGUGUCAUCCGGGAUUGUUGGAAUUUUGCAUGUGUCUGUUCCAUAUCCCGCUGGUAACCAGCUUACAGACCUUCUGUCAGGUUGGCUUACAUUAUCAUCAACAGGUUGCCGUAGUGAUGAUAUGAUGCUGGACACAAUCAUUGUGCACUUUGUUAAUUUGGUAUGGUGGUGCCACACAUUAUCACUGUACAGCAUUAACAAGGCUGGAAUAUGGCCCUCUGCUGUAGGGGGCGUGGCACCUGUGACUUGCACUGGAAUAAGUAGGAGGCUUUCCCCAAAGGAUAUGGAGACUGAUGUGUGCUCCAUAUCUUGAGGGGAGCUCUCUUGGUUUCCUUUGGCCGGGUCUGUUAGUUACUUUUGAAGGCCAUGCCAACCCUUUUAGGCCAUUAAAUUUUUCUCAAACAAUAGCCAGCCUCAUUUCUGCUUCAUCUCUGUGGUAGGAACCAUUCCCUACUCUUACUCCCUCCUCUUGUCCAACUUCCACCAAACACUCAAUCCGAGUCCUGGCUGCUUUCUUGCUUAGGUCUGUGGCUGGUCACUGUGGUGAAAGAGUCAAGGUGGGCAGUGUUUGGGGUAGGAAAUGAGUAGUGGUGAAGCAGCAGCAGUGUGUGUGUGGGUGUGGGUGUGUGUGCAUGCGUGUGCAUUUGCAUGUGUGUAUGUUGACAAAUGAGAGUGUAGCCAUAAGAUUUCAUUGUUACUACUAGUCUUUGUGUACCUAUCUGGAGGGACAUUAAAAAAAUAUGGCCAUUCUCCCAUCUAGGGGGUUCCCAUCUCAGACUUCUCUGAUAAGAGUAAUUUGAGAACAAAUACAGAUUCAUCUAUGGGAAAAGAUGUUUAAACUCAGCAUGAAGGAGAAACAAAUUUAGGAGUGGAAAGCAAGGCAGGUAGUUAGGUGAUUUCCAUGACCACAUUUGCUUGGGCCAGGGAAGUGGUGCACCUCUUUUAUAACAAUGGGAGAUUUCAGAAACAGUUUGAGUGUUGGCAGACCAAUGCCCUGAUAAGCUUGUGGUAUAGAGGUAGGAAGGGAGGGAGGCCAGAGAUUAGAUAAAAUGAUGGUGGGUGGGAUCUUAGCUCUAAAUGAAAAGAACUGGACUUACUAAGUGGGUGGAUUACUUGCUAGCCAUAACUUUUAGGGAAGGGUAGGUCUGGAGAGAAGGUGAAGACCAGCAGAAAUAUACUGUGAAAUUGCCAAAUAUGUUUGGUUGCAGAAAACACAGCCUGGCUCUUUGUGGCUAGAUGUGACUUCCAACUUCUGAAGACAGGAUUGCCAAGAGAUGUGAUCUUUCCACAUACAGCUCCUGUCCCCAUCUCUUUAUGUGUAGAGACCUGGAUUUGGGGUAGUGGGGUAGUAAACCAUAUAUUUCCAAAAGAUGGUGUGAAGAGUCGUUUCUCUUCGUCUGGGAUGUGAUUGGCUUUUGUUUUUUGUUUUUUGUUUUUGAGACGGAGUCUCGCUCUGUCGCUUUGUCACCAGGCUGGAGUGCAAUGGCACAAUCUCAGCUCACUGCAACCUCCGCCUCCUGGCUUCAAGUGAUUCUCCUGCCUCAGCCUCCUGAGUAGCUGGGACUAUAGGCGCGCACCACCAUGCCCAGCUAAUUUUUGUAUUUUUAGUAGAGAUGGGAUUUCACCAUGUUGGCCAGGAUGGUCUUGAUCUCUUGACCUCAUGAUCCACCCGCCUUGGCCUCCCAAAGUGCUGGGAUUACAGGCUUGAGCUACUGCGCCCGGCCAGUGAUUGGCUUUUAAAUUAAUCACAAAUGUUUGAUAAAAUUCUGGUAUGUGCUAAGUCCCAGGCUUGGUUGAUAUCUCAGACUAUGAUAGCUGUGACCUUCAAGAAAUUUCUGGCUUGGGGAAUCUGUAGUUUCUGGUUGUCCAAAAAAGAUAGUUCUUAGUCCUACUUUAUUUUCUACCCACUCAACUCUCCAGACUUCCCUCUUAGUAAAGGAAUUCAUAAUUCUCCCUGCAUCUUCUCUGUUUAUUUCAAUGUCCAUGUUCUGAGUCUCAAGUUUUCCUGAAGCACAGGAGCAGGCUUGGCCCCAGAGCCCCUGGCUUUUUCAACGAGCAUCAGAAAUGCUAUCAAUAUAUUCUCUCUGUUGCUUUAUCAGCUUCUCUAAAUUUAUUUUGUAAGGAAGUUAGCACCUCCUUCCAGGACUUUAAACAGUUGUCUUUGCCAAUUUGUUCCUGGAUUUUCCUUGAACUUCUCAGGUUUCCAAGCCACAUCCUAGCAGGGCAUCCAGGAGCCUUGCACUGAACCUCUCAGCUCUUUUGACUUUCUUCUGGUCAUAGGUGUUGGGCCUCCCAUUAGGUAGAAGUCCUUUGAGCAGACCCGAAAUGGCCAAAUGAGACAUCAUCCAAGUUCCUCCCUCCUUUACUGUCUCGGCUUUUUCAAGCACCCCUUUCACCUCUCUUUUCUGCCUUUUCCUCAGUCUGUCAAGUUCUUUGGAGGAAAGAAGUUCUUGGUCAGAGGUCCUAAAACCACCACCAGCUGGGGGUGCUGAGAAUGGUGAGGAGUUGGACAGUCCCGGGGCUUUUUUGAAAGGGGACUUUAUGGUCAUUUCCCCUGUUUAGGGUGAGGGACUAAGAAUUCUCAAGCCUUCAGUUUCAUCCAUAUUUCAAUGUAAGCAGAAAAGCACAUCUCAAAGCCAAAUAGAAAUGAUUUUCUACUAAGCCUAUCCUUUGUGAUUCUUGGUUCCCUUGGUCUCUUAAUAUUAAUUAUAGAGAAUGGGCAGUUGAGUCAGUUAACAUCUUUUCAUCAGAAAGGAGGGUAAUAUUCAUAACCAAAAGAGAUGUAAAGGAAGUAUAUUACUGCUUGAAGUGUGAAAAGAGGAAAGGAGUGUUAUGUGAACCUUUUCAGUAGGGAAAUUCAGAAAAUGGAAUGAUUCAUCCAUAGGCAUAAUUCUUUUAGGAGAUUCUGUGCUCAAAGGGAAGGGAAUGGUUUCUGAUCCUUCUGAAGAGAAAAGGAAUAGCAUUUUUCUUAAACCUAACCCAGUUUCAGCAUUGGAGAAUACAGAACUUUUUCUUCUAGCUGAUGGCAUUAAUAUUUCUUGAGAGAGAGAACUCACCCAUGGCACUUUUCUGAGCCCAGCAGAAAUCAGCGGAGCUUGGGCUUCGCUUAGCAGGUUUGCAAUUGACUUCAACAUGCAGGCUUUUCACAUGUGCAAUAAUGCUGGAAACAGAAGCACCAAACUGAUUGUGCAAUUACUCCUUUUGUAGAAGAGGCCAAAAUCCUCCUCCUCCUUCCUUUCUCCUAUAUUCACUCCUCCAGGAUCAUAAAGCCUCCCUCUUGUUUAUCUGUGUCUGUCUGUCUGAUUGGUUAGAUUUGGCUGCCCUUCCAAGCUAAUGGUGUCAGGUGGAGAACAGAGCAACCUUCCCUCGGAAGGAGACAAUUCGAGGUGCUGGUACAUUUCCCUUGUUUUCUAUGUUCUUCUUUCUAGUGGGUCUCAUGUAGAGAUAGAGAUAUUUUUUUGUUUUAGAGAUUCCAAAGUAUAUAUUUUUAGUGUAAGAAAUGUACCCUCUCCACACUCCAUGAUGUAAAUAGAACCAGGAAUAAAUGUGUCAUUGUGAUAAUCCCAUAGCAAUUUAUGGUAAGAACAAGACCCCUUUCCCUCACCACCGAGUCUCGUGGUCUGUGUCUGUGAACCAGGGCAGGUAAUUGUGACACUGCAUCUCAUAGAACUCUGCCUGCCCAGAUUUUUGUGUGCUCACCUCAAUGGGUGAAAAAUAAAGUCUGUGUAAACUGUU